GAGGUGACCACAACAUGGCUGCGGCGCCUGGGCUGCUCGUCUGGCUGCUCGUGCUCCGGCUGCCCUGGCGGGUGCCGGGCCAGCUGGACCCCAGCACUGGCCGGCGGUUCUCGGAGCACAAACUCUGCGCGGACGACGAAUGCAGCAUGUUAAUGUACCGCGGUGAGGCUCUUGAAGAUUUCACAGGCCCGGAUUGUCGUUUUGUGAAUUUUAAAAAAGGUGAUCCUGUAUAUGUUUACUAUAAACUGGCAAGAGGAUGGCCUGAAGUUUGGGCUGGAAGUGUUGGACGCACUUUUGGAUAUUUUCCAAAAGAUUUAAUCCAGGUAGUUCAUGAAUAUACCAAAGAAGAGCUACAAGUUCCAACAGAUGAGACGGAUUUUGUUUGUUUUGAUGGAGGAAGAGAUGAUUUUCAUAAUUAUAAUGUAGAAGAACUUUUAGGGUUUUUGGAACUGUACAAUUCUGCAGCUACAGAUUCUGAGAAAGCUGUAGAAAAAACUUUACAGGAUAUGGAAAAAAACCCUGAAUUAUCUAAGGAAAGGGAACCUGAACCUGAACCAGUAGAAGCCAACUCAGAGGAAAGUGAUAGUGUAUUCUCAGAAAACACUGAGGAUCUUCAGGAACAGUUUACAACUCAGAAGCACCACUCCCAUGCAAACAGCCAAGCAAAUCAUGCUCAGGGAGAGCAGGCUUCAUUUGAAUCUUUUGAAGAAAUGCUGCAAGAUAAACUAAAAGUGCCAGAAAGUGAAAACAACAAAACCAGCAAUAGUUCUCAGGUCUCAAAUGAACAGGAUAAGAUUGAUGCCUAUAAACUUUUGAAAAAAGAAAUGACUCUAGACUUGAAAACCAAAUUUGGCUCAACAGCUGAUGCACUUGUAUCUGAUGAUGAGACAACCAGACUCGUUACUUCAUUAGAAGAUGAUUUUGAUGAGGAAUUGGAUACUGAGUAUUAUGCAGUUGGAAAGGAAGAUGAGGAGAACCAAGAAGACUUUGAUGAGUUGCCAUUACUUACCUUUACAGAUGGGGAAGAUAUGAAAACUCCAGCAAAGUCUGGCGUUGAGAAAUAUCCAACAGAUAAAGAGCAGAAUUCAAAUGAAGAGGACAAGGUUCAGCUAACUGUGCCCCCUGGCAUCAAAAAUGAUGAUAAAAAUAUACUAACAACCUGGGGGGACACUAUCUUCUCUAUUGUCACAGGAGGUGAAGAAACAAGAGAUACGAUGGAUUUAGAGAGCUCUAGUUCAGAGGAAGAAAAAGAAGAUGAUGAUGAUGCAUUAGUCCCAGAUAGCAAACAGGGGAAACCACAGUCAGCAACAGAUUAUAGUGACCCUGACAAUGUAGAUGAUGGUCUUUUUAUUGUAGACAUUCCUAAAACAAAUAAUGACAAAGAAGUAAACGCAGAACAUCACAUUAAAGGAAAAGGGAGGGGAGUUCAGGAAUCCAAGAGGGGCCUGGUACAAGAUAAGACAGAAUUAGAGGAUGAAAAUCAAGAAGGCAUGACUGUGCACAGUUCUGUUCACAGCAAUAACCUCAACUCUAUGCCAGCUGCUGAAAAGGGUAAAGACACAUUAAAAUCAGCUUAUGAUGAUACAGAAAAUGACCUAAAAGGAGCAGCUAUUCAUAUCUCAAAAGGAAUGCUCCACGAAGAAAAGCCUGGAGAGCAGAUUUUGGAAGGUGGCUCAGAGAGUGAAUCUGCACAGAAAGCUGCAGGGAAUCAAAUGAAUGACAGAAAGAUUCAACAGGAAUCCCUGGGUAGUGCACCACUCAUGGGAGAUGACCACCCUAACGCAUCCAGAGACAGUGUGGAGGGAGACGCUUUGGUAAAUGGGGCCAAACUGCACACGCUUUCAGUGGAGCAUCAACGUGAGGAAUUGAAAGAGGAAUUAGUUCUUAAAACUCAAAACCAACCUAGAUUCUCCUCUCCAGAUGAGAUUGAUUUGCCCAGAGAACUGGAAGACGAGGUUCCCAUUCUGGGAAGAAAUCUUCCCUGGCAACAAGAAAGAGAUGUGGCUGCCACAGCCAGUAAGCAAAUGAGUGAGAAGAUAAGGCUCUCUGAGGGAGAAGCCAAAGAGGACUCCUUGGAUGAAGAGUUUUUUCAUCACAAGGCAAUGCAGGGCACAGAGGUAGGACAGACAGACCAAACUGACAGCACAGGAGGACCAGCUUUCCUUUCUAAAGUAGAAGAGGAUGAUUAUCCCUCUGAAGAACUACUAGAGGAUGAAAACGCUAUAAAUGCAAAACGGUCUAAAGAAAAAAACCCUGGGAAUCAGGGCAGGCAGUUUGAUGUUAAUCUGCAAGUCCCUGACAGAGCAGUUUUAGGGACCAUUCAUCCAGAUCCAGAAAUUGAAGAAAGCAAGCAAGAAACUAGUAUGAUUUUGGAUAGCGAAAAAACAAGUGAGACUGCUGCCAAAGGGGUCAACACAGGAGGCAGGGAACCAAAUACAAUGGUGGAAAAAGAACGCCCUCUGGCAGAUAAGAAAGCACAGAGACCAUUUGAACGAAGUGACUUUUCUGACAGCAUAAAAAUUCAGACUCCAGAAUUAGGUGAAGUGUUUCAGAAUAAAGAUUCUGAUUAUCUGAAGAACGACAACCCUGAGGAACAUCUGAAGACCUCAGGGCUUGCAGGGGAGCCUGAGGGAGAACUCUCAAAAGAGGACCAUGAGAACACAGAGAAGUACAUGGGCACAGAAAGCCAGGGGUCUGCUGCUGCAGAACCUGAAGAUGACUCGUUCCACUGGACUCCACAUACAAGUGUAGAGCCAGGGCAUAGUGACAAGAGGGAGGACUUACUUAUCAUAAGCAGCUUCUUUAAAGAACAACAGUCUUUGCAGCGGUUCCAGAAGUACUUUAAUGUCCAUGAGCUGGAAGCCUUGCUACAAGAAAUGUCAUCAAAACUGAAGUCAGCGCAGCAGGAGAGCCUGCCCUAUAAUAUGGAAAAAGUCCUAGAUAAGGUCUUCCGUGCUUCUGAGUCACAAAUUCUGAGCAUAGCAGAAAAAAUGCUUGAUACUCGUGUGGCUGAAAAUAGAGAUCUGGGAAUGAACGAAAAUAACAUAUUUGAAGAGGCUGCAGUGCUUGAUGACAUUCAAGACCUCAUCUAUUUUGUCAGGUACAAGCACUCCACAGCAGAGGAGACAGCCACACUGGUGAUGGCACCACCUCUAGAGGAAGGCUUGGGUGGAGCAAUGGAAGAGAUGCAACCACUGCAUGAAGAUAAUUUCUCACGAGAGAAGACAGCAGAACUUAAUGUGCAGGUUCCUGAAGAACCCACCCACUUGGACCAACGUGUGAUUGGGGACACUCAUGCCUCAGAAGUGUCACAGAAGCCAAAUACUGAGAAAGACCUGGACCCAGGGCCAGUUACAACAGAAGACACUCCUAUGGAUGCUAUUGAUGCAAACAAGCAACCAGAGACAGCCGCCGAAGAGCCGGCAAGUGUCACACCUUUGGAAAACGCAAUCCUUCUAAUAUAUUCAUUCAUGUUUUAUUUAACUAAGUCGCUAGUUGCUACAUUGCCUGAUGAUGUUCAGCCUGGGCCUGAUUUUUAUGGACUGCCAUGGAAACCUGUAUUUAUCACUGCCUUCUUGGGAAUUGCUUCGUUUGCCAUUUUCUUAUGGAGAACUGUCCUUGUUGUGAAGGAUAGAGUAUAUCAAGUCACGGAACAGCAAAUUUCUGAGAAGUUGAAGACUAUCAUGAAAGAAAAUACAGAACUUGUACAAAAAUUGUCAAAUUAUGAACAGAAGAUCAAGGAAUCAAAGAAACAUGUUCAGGAAACCAGGAAACAAAAUAUGAUUCUCUCUGAUGAAGCAAUUAAAUAUAAGGAUAAAAUCAAGACACUUGAAAAAAAUCAGGAAAUUCUGGAUGACACAGCUAAAAAUCUUCGUGUUAUGCUAGAAUCUGAGAGAGAACAGAAUGUCAAGAAUCAGGACUUGAUAUCAGAAAACAAGAAAUCUAUAGAGAAGUUAAAGGAUGUUAUUUCAAUGAAUGCCUCAGAAUUUUCAGAGGUUCAGAUUGCACUUAAUGAAGCUAAGCUUAGUGAAGAGAAGGUGAAGUCUGAAUGCCAUCGGGUUCAAGAAGAAAAUGCUAGGCUUAAGAAGAAAAAAGAGCAGUUGCAGCAGGAAAUCGAAGACUGGAGUAAAUUACAUGCUGAGCUCAGUGAGCAAAUCAAAUCAUUUGAGAAGUCUCAGAAAGAUUUGGAAGUAGCUCUUACUCACAAGGAUGAUAAUAUUAAUGCUUUGACUAACUGCAUUACACAGUUGAAUCUGUUAGAGUGUGAAUCUGAAUCUGAGGGUCAAAAUAAAGGUGGAAAUGAUUCAGAUGAAUUAGCAAAUGGAGAAGUGGGAGGUGACCGGAAUGAGAAGAUGAAAAAUCAAAUUAAGCAGAUGAUGGAUGUCUCUCGGACACAGACUGCAAUAUCGGUAGUUGAAGAGGAUCUAAAGCUUUUACAGCUUAAGCUAAGAGCCUCCGUGUCCACUAAAUGUAACCUGGAAGACCAGGUAAAGAAAUUGGAAGAUGACCGCAACUCACUACAAGCUGCCAAAGCUGGACUGGAAGAUGAAUGCAAAACCUUGAGGCAGAAAGUGGAGAUUCUGAAUGAGCUCUAUCAGCAGAAGGAGAUGGCUUUGCAAAAGAAACUGAGUCAAGAAGAGUAUGAACGGCAAGAAAGAGAGCACAGGCUGUCAGCUGCAGAUGAAAAGGCAGUUUCGGCUGCAGAGGAAGUAAAAACUUACAAGCGGAGAAUUGAAGAAAUGGAGGAUGAAUUACAGAAGACAGAGCGGUCAUUUAAAAACCAGAUCGCUACCCAUGAGAAGAAAGCUCAUGAAAACUGGCUCAAAGCUCGUGCUGCAGAAAGAGCUAUAGCUGAAGAGAAAAGGGAAGCUGCCAAUUUGAGACACAAAUUAUUAGAAUUAACACAAAAGAUGGCAAUGCUGCAAGAAGAACCUGUGAUUGUAAAACCAAUGCCAGGAAAACCAAAUACACAAAACCCUCCACGGAGAGGUCCUCUGAGCCAGAAUGGCUCUUUUGGCCCAUCCCCUGUGAGUGGUGGAGAAUGCUCCCCUCCAUUGACAGUGGAGCCACCCGUGAGACCUCUCUCUGCUACUCUCAAUCGAAGAGAUAUGCCUAGAAGUGAAUUUGGAUCAGUGGACGGGCCUCUACCUCAUCCUCGAUGGUCAGCUGAGGCAUCUGGGAAACCCUCUCCUUCUGAUCCAGGAUCUGGUACAGCUACCAUGAUGAACAGCAGCUCAAGAGGCUCUUCCCCUACCAGGGUACUCGAUGAAGGCAAGCAAACUGUUCUCCAAGAGCCUGAAGUCCCCUCAGUUCCCAGCAUUACAUCUUUGGCUGAGCGUCCAGUAGCAGUUAAUAUGGCUCCAAAAGGGCCCCCUCCUUUCCCAGGAGUCCCUCUCAUGAGCACCCCCAUGGGAGGCCCUGUACCACCACCCAUUCGAUAUGGACCACCACCUCAGCUCUGCGGACCUUUUGGGCCUCGGCCACUUCCUCCACCCUUUGGCCCUGGUAUGCGUCCACCACUAGGCUUAAGAGAAUUUGCACCAGGCGUUCCACCAGGAAGACGGGACCUGCCUCUCCACCCUCGGGGAUUUUUACCUGGACACGCACCAUUUAGACCUUUAGGUUCACUUGGCCCAAGAGAGUACUUUAUUCCUGGUACCCGAUUACCACCCCCAACCCAUGGUCCCCAGGAAUACCCACCACCACCUGCUGUAAGAGACUUACUGCCGUCAGGCUCUAGAGAUGAGCCUCCACCUGCCUCUCAGAGCACUAGCCAGGACUGUUCACAGGCUUUAAAACAGAGCCCAUAAAACUAUGACCUCUGAGGUUUCAUUGGAAAGAAAGUGUACUGUGCAUUAUCCAUUACAGUAAAGGAUUUCAUUGGCUUCAAAAUCCAAAAGUUUAUUUUAAAAGGUUUGUUGUUAGAACUAAGCUGCCUUGGCAGUGUGCAUUUUUGAGCCAAACAAUUCAAAAAUGUCAUUUCUUCCCUAAAUAAAAAUCACCUUUUAAGCUAGAGCGUCCUUACAACUUUGAAAUGUGCAAUAAAGAAUACCUGUGUUUUAGCUAAUGUAGCAUAUGUAAUUGCAAAAUGAUUUAGAAUGUCAUGAAAAAUAUGAACAUUUCCUGUGGAAAUGCUUUAAGAACAUGUAUUUCCAUUAUCCUAUUUUUAGUGUACACCAGCUGAAUACGGAGCAAUGGUGUUUAUAAGCGUUUUUUUAAACUAUCUGGUCACAAAGACUGUUACGCUAAAAAUGUUUACUAAAAGAUCACUAAACUAUCUCCCCUCUUGCUGAAGUUCUUUGUAGUAAUAGCUCAUAAAAAUUUGUUUAUUAAUAUUUCCCAAGUGUCUGUUGACUCAUUGGACUGUUAUGAGGCUUGUGCCAUUUGGGGAACAUGUAAACUCAGGCUCCCAGAACUGAAGAUGGUGGCUGGUGGCACACUUCCGGCUGCUCCUCCGUCACCUGUGAACUCUACAAGUGACGUCUUUUUAUUUCAAAGAAGUUUAUUUCCCACUUGUAUAGCAUUCACAUGCUUUCUUUACGAUCCUCAUUGUCUAUUUGAGAAUGGUUUUCUGAGAGUGAGUUUACAUUAGUAGCAAGAGUUGUUUGACCUGAUGUUCCAUUGUUUUUACCAUUCCUGUAGAAAAAGGGUGCACAACAGAAAAAUGAAAAUGAUGUGUCAUGGCCAUAAAAGUAUAGAAAUCUUUAAAAAUUUUAAAAUGUACAGUCCCUUAUCUAUCUUUCCCAUUCCUUGCCACUGAUUUUUGAGGAAUAUAAUAAAAAGAUUGGAAGAGUAUAAUGCCAUGAGAAAGAAUGAUUUAGGACUGUGAGGGUUAUAACAUGCCCUAGGUCAGCAACCAAGGGUUGAAAUCAGUUCUGUUUUAGGGGGAAAUGGGGGCGACAGAUAUUAUUCCAAAAUUAAUAUUAAUUAAUAUUUAAACGUUGGUGUUUUUAUUUAAAAAUCAGUAACUAACCAUCUGGAAUUGCACCAUACUUAAAGUCUUAUCCAUUACUACACUGUCUUUAAAACAAUGUUUCUUUAAAUACUCUACAACGUUUCUAAGAACGAACUUCAGACAUUUUAAUUACAGUAAUAAUAGCACUCCUUUUAAGGAGUUUCAGAUCCACACUAAAACUAAAAUCAUAAAAGGCUGAUACUUUUGUUUGCUGCUAGGCUAUAUUCUUCCAUUCUUUGAAGUCCUAUGAUGUAAUAUUUUUGAAACCUAGUGUAUGUCUUGUCACUGUUGUGAUAUUUAAUCGAUUAAGAAUACCUUGUAAAAAGGAGCAAAAGCUUCAAUGUGAAACAAUUUUCUCUCUUUAUACUAAACAACUGAAGAUAGAUAGUUUAGAAAGAUAAGGACCUUUGAAAGAAGACAACUCUGUCAAAGUUCAUAAGGAAUAUAAAAAUUCUUCAGGAAAAGAGAAUUCAAUCUAUAUGUCCUCCCGUUUAAUAUCAAGAAUAGAAGAAAUUAAGAGGAAAACUCCACAGAAGAGCAUAGGCCACUUUUAGCCAUGUAAAAAUAAGAUUAAGUCACAAAUACAACUUUUGAAUUUACCUGUCAAUAUCUCUUUAGGACACAAAACAAUGCUGAAGUUAAUAUAAUUUCUAAUUUUAAAUGUCAUUUAAGUGUAGAUUAUGCCAUCUAGGAAGGUAAGUAGGAAAGGUAAAUUAAAUCUAUUUUUAAAAUUCAAAAUAUUAGAGUAUUUUUCCCCUCUAAAGCCUUUUUUGGUGAUUAUUCUGUAUCUGACAUAAUUGAGAAACUGGUAAGCUGUAAAGAUUCCAGUGUAGCUUCUCUGAGAAGUUGUGAGCCAGUCCAUAACUGCUUCCUCACAUCCAUCUGAUUGCACCAUUUCUGCAGCAAACCCCAAAGCAGGGUGCCAAUAUGCAGAUGGCAUAGGGAGUAUCAUCCCUCAGCCAAAUCACUUUUCCAUCUCUAAAGUUUCAUCUAUUUUGGAAGUCAUCUCCAACUAAUUGUGUCUGGAUUUAGUUGCUAAAAUUGUCUUAUUUAUGAAGCAGCAAUAUUCAGCCUGAAAGCAUUUCUGCCAUAGUUGUUGUAGUUAUAUCGCCAAUGGCUGAUUUUUUUCAUUGGAAAGUAAAUUUAAGUAAUUCGUGGGAUGUGGUAUAUUCUGUGUCAACUUCAAGAUAAUCACUCAUUUUCUCGUUAUAUUCAGGUCUGAAUUAAAGUUAAGUUAAUCACA